AGAGACCCGCUCGGUCCCGACCGAGAGCUGGCGUCAGGAGCCGCAGGGUCACAGCGUGUCUUUGAAGCUGCCUCCGCCGCCACCAUGAGCGGCCGAAGUCGGGGUCGAAAGUCCUCCCGCGCCAAAAACCGGGGCAAAGGCCGCGCCAAAGCCCGAGUCCGCCCUGCUCCGGACGACGCCCCGCGCGACCCGGACCCUUCACAGUACCAGAGUCUCGGGGAAGACACCCAGGCGGCACAGGUGCAGGCUGGCGCGGGGUGGGGUGGCCUGGAAGCCGCUGCGUCCGCGCAGCUCCUCCGGCUCGGGGAGGAGGCCGCCUGCCGGCUCCCCCUGGACUGUGGCCUCGCGCUGCGGGCCCGAGCUGCGGGGGACCACGGGCAGGCCGCGGCCAGGCCCGGCCCGGGGAAGGCCGCAUCUCUCUCGGAGCGCCUGGCCGCAGACACUGUCUUCGUGGGAACAGCGGGAACCGUGGGAAGGCCGAAAAAUGCCCCCCGCGUUGGAAACCGGCGUGGCCCUGCCGGGAAGAAGGCCCCAGAAACCUGUAGCACCGCGGGGAGGGGGCCUCAGGUCAUAGCUGGUGGGAGGCAGAAGAAAGGGGCGGCAGGGGAGAAUACCUCGGUGUCAGCUGGGGAGGAAAAGAAGGAAGAGAGGGAUGCAGGGUCGGGGCCCCCAGCGACGGAAGGCAGCAUGGAUACGCUGGAGAACGUGCAGCUGAAGCUGGAGAACAUGAACGCCCAGGCGGACAGGGCCUACCUUCGGCUCUCCAGGAAGUUUGGGCAGUUGCGACUGCAGCACUUGGAGCGCAGGAACCACCUCAUCCAAAAUAUCCCGGGCUUCUGGGGGCAAGCAUUUCAGAACCAUCCCCAGCUAGCAUCCUUUCUGAAUAGCCAAGAGAAAGAGGUACUGAGCUACUUAAACAGCUUGGAAGUGGAAGAGCUCGGCCUUGCCAGAUUGGGCUACAAAAUCAAGUUCUACUUCGAUCGCAACCCGUAUUUCCAAAAUAAGGUGCUCAUCAAGGAAUAUGGGUGUGGUCCUUCUGGCCAGGUGGUGUCUCGUUCUACUCCAAUCCAGUGGCUCCCAGGGCAUGAUCUCCAGUCCCUAAGCCAGGGAAACCCAGAAAACAACCGUAGUUUCUUUGGGUGGUUUUCAAACCACAGCUCCAUUGAGUCUGACAAGAUUGUGGAGAUAAUCAACGAAGAAUUGUGGCCCAAUCCCUUGCAGUUCUACCUUUUGAGUGAAGGGGCUCGUGUAGAGAAAGGAAAGGAAAAAGAAGGCAGGCAAGGUCCAGGAAAGCAGCCAAUGGAGACUACUCAGCCUGGGGUGAGCCAAUCCAACUGAUCCUGCACAAGUCUCCCUGCUACCUCCUGCUGGGCUGCUCCUGGUUGACUACAUAUUUGGCUCUCUGCCUUCUCUUCAUGUUGGCCUCUGUGUACUAUAGACCCUUUGGACUUUAGUUACAAGAAUAUGGCAUUUAUGAUCAUGUUCUUUUGCCUCCCAUAGCCUCUUGCUUUUCUACGUUAGUGUCACAUGUUAUGUGAUCGCACCCGGACUGUUCAUAUGUUAAGCACACAUACUUUAGAUGUGUGCUCCCUGUUAUCUACAUUGCCUGGACCUUGUUCUUGGCUCUGGCCUUUCCUACUUGUCUUUAACAUGGACACUCAUGAGUCAUCCUCCAGGACGACCAGUGCAUCCUCAAGCUCUGCUCCUUCAGGGCCAGUGACUUGCUGGGCUUCGUGUUCAUGCUGGCCAUGCAUGUCAUCUAUGCAAGCGUUUCCAUUGCCACUGCAGAAUGAAGCCAGUGCACAUGGUAUUAGUCAUCAGCCAGAACUUCCUGUUCUGUGGGUCUGGGGUCACCAGCUGAGAUGUCACCUGCUUUAUUUCUGGCUUUGGCCUGUGGUCUGUGAUACCCAUCCUGCUUGAUGUUCUGCAGAAUGGCACUUGACUGCUGGGCAUGCAUGAAGUUAAGGGCAAGAAACAGUAUGCCAUGUGUUCUGUACCAUCAUGUGUCUCUUCUUGCUUCUGGGCCCUUCUACUGGUGAACUUUCAUCAAGAUCUGCGCCAUGCCGUGUCACUAUCAAGCCAUUAAGUUUUGUCUGGGUUGCUGUCAGCCCCAGUUGGCUUCCUGGUCAACAAGGACCUCAAGAACUGCCUGUGGACCGAGGCCCCCUACCAGUGCAUGAGACACACACCUACCCUCCCCAGCUUUCCAGGAACCCUACUGGCUGCCAGACUGAUGGGCGGGCUGGUAUGUGUGGACAUGUGUUCACUGUCAUUAUGCUGUGGCUCCAGGUGAGGGUGAGGACUGGGCCUAUAUAGAAUCCAGAUACCAUUGUCAACUUCCCUUAUUCCCGUCUAAGAUGUGAGCAGAGUGCCAUAGUAGGGGUUCUGGGAAGAGGUAUUUCUGAUUUGUGGGCCUCUGCUUGCUUGACUUCAGGUCACUUAUACUUCUUAUUUUGCUUGCCUGCCUUCAUCCCUCAUUUCCUCCCUCUCAUUCUUCUUUCCUCCCUCCCUUUCCUGGUAGCCUCCUUUCCUCCCCUUCUGCCUUCCCCUUCCUUCUUUCCUUAUUCUUUUUUAUUUUGUUUAAAUAGUACCACAGAGAAAACAACUGAAAAACCACAUUUUUCUACAUACAGCUGGGGAGGUAGCUGAGAACUUGGCACUGCGCACACAUACUAGGUUGAAAGAGAGUUGAGGAAACCAGAAGGCCAAGUGGAUCUGCUGGCAAACCCUGAACCUGUCUCCUGCGCUUGCUCUACAGUUCUGAAGUUGAAAAUCCUUUUCAUGCCUAGCAUCUGCUUGAGUUAUAAACCCCAAGGCAGCCAUGUCAUAGACUAGUGUUUACUCUUGUUUUGACUUUGUUUUAAUGCUUCCUAAGACCCAAGUGCCUCCUGCUGUUUCCUCCUUUGUGGUAGCCUCUGGCCAUCUGGACCUCAAUCCCCAGCUUUCCCACUUUCAGCAGUCCUUUGCUCUCUUUGCUUCUACCUCAAAUAGCCCCAGGAGUGGGCUUUAGUCUCCAAUAUGGAGCAUCUCAAGCUUCUCCUGGGGGAUGGGGAUUGGGAUGGGCAGAAUCUGUUUUGGAUCUCCGGGUUAUUUCCAGUGGGUGUAAAAGCAGAGCUGGGCCUUUCCCUCUCUUAUCCCUGAGGGUGGGUAAGAAGGACUGUAUCUACACCUGUUCUUCCCUACCUUCUCUUUUGUUAGGGAGGCCUCAUUCUAAGUUCCUCAAGAGAGUCCUUGGCUUAAAGCUGUAGCAAGGGUGUGCUAGGUGGGGGAUUUGGAGCAAAACCGUCGAGUAGGCAUGAUACUGGUAUGGAGUGGGCCUGCAAAAUCAGACAGAAAUGGCUUGAGAAGCCGCAGGGGGAGCAUGCCUGUCUCUCAGUGAUAGAGUAUGGGAGGGACCUCCCUAGCUUGGAAAAUGAGAAUUGAAGGGGUUAUGAACAAAUAGGAUGCCUAGUUGAGGAUGUUCCCAAAGUUUUGUCCAAUCUUAUCAUUAGUAGAUUUUAUAAGCCACAGAGACAAACCAGAAACGGAAUAAUGUUACUUUGGAUGCUUUAUUUUUUUGUUCUAGGUGUGGCUUUGUACAUGCAGAAGAAUGCUAUAUGCUGCACAUUUUGCCUUUAAAGUCUUACGACUUUCCCCAUUUUAGUCUAAUGGGAAGAUACAGAUGUGCAAGUCUGCUUUUUUGUUUUUUGUUAUUAUUUUUUUUUUUUUGCUCUGUGUUAUGGACAUUUUCAGACAUGCACAGAAGUGGAGAGGAUGGUCCUUGGACCCCAUGUGUCCAUCACCUAGCUGCAUCACUUAUCAGCUAUGGUCAACCUGGUUUCAUCUGUAUCUCUCUCUUUUCACCUGUAUUGUUUAUUGAAAAUCCAAGACACUAUGCCAAUGCAACCGUGACUACUUUGGGAGAUUGGUAGUCUCUUUUGAUGGUGAUAGUGAUGGGGUGCACUAUCAUAAUCACAUCAGGUCUGCUUUUUGCUUUUAAUGUUAACUAAUGAAGUUCCAGAGAUGGGCCUUAGAAAUGUGUUUUAAGAAUUAACAAGGAGUCUCAAAAAGAAAUGAGAGGGAUGCUUCCUUUCCCUUGCAUCUACAAAACAAGAGAGAGACUGUUCUGUUGUAAAACUCUUUCAAAAAUUCUGAUAUGGUAAGGUACUUGAGACCCUUCACCAGAAUGUCAAUCUUUUUUUCUGUGUAACAUGGAAACUUGUGUGACCAUUAGCAUUGUUAUCAGCUUGUACUGGUCUCAUAACUCUGGUUUUGGAAGAAUAAUUUGGAAAUUGUUGCUGUGUUCUGUGAAAAUAACCUCCCCAAAAUAAUUAGUAACUGGUUGUUCUACUUGGUAAUUUGACACCCUGUUAAUAACGCAAUUAUUUCUGUGUUCUUAAACAGUAUAAAUAGUUGUAAGUUUGCAUGCAUGAUGGAAAAAUAAAAACCUGUAUCUCUGUUA